ACUCCACGGGGAGCCCCAACGCUGGCAGGAGAGGAUCCUACAGGACAGCAAGGAGAUGCCACCUAAAAACAAAGAAAAAGGGAAGAAAUCUGGGGCACAGAAGAAGAAAAAGAACUGGGGUGCAGAUGUGGUGGCCGAGUCCAGGCACAGGCUGGUGGUGCUGGAGAAGGAGCUGCUCCGAGACCACUUGGCUCUACGGAGGGAUGAAGCCCGUCGAGCCAAGGCUUCCGAAGACCAGCUGAGGCAGAGGCUGCAAGGGGUGGAGGCUGAGCUGGAAGGGGCCCGAAGUGAAGGGAAGGCCAUAUAUGCAGAGAUGAGUCGCCAGUGCCAUGCCCUGCAGGAGGAUAUGCAAACCCGCAGCAAGCAGCUGGAGGAAGAAGUCAAAGGCCUUCGGGGGCAGCUAGAGGCAUGCCAAAGGGAGGCUGCAGCUGCCCGGGAAGAGGCUGAACAAGCUCUCGGAGAGCGGGACCAGGCCCUGGCUCAGCUUCGGGCCCACAUGGCAGACAUGGAGGCGAAGUAUGAGGAAAUCUUACACGACAGUCUGGACAGGCUCUUGGCCAAGCUGAGAGCCAUCAAGCAGCAGUGGGAUGGGGCAGCACUGAGACUUCACGCCAGGCACAAGGAGCAGCAACGCCAGUUUGGACUCACCCCCCCUGGAUCUUUGAGGCCACCAGCCCCUAGUCUCUAGUGUUCUCUGAGGCCCCAGCAAUAAAGUGUCUUGAUGUAGAACUCAA